AUUUUCUUCUGCACUUCUGUCUGGAGAGGUCUGUAGCCACUGAGGGCCCCGGUCGGGGCCGCUUUGCAGGUCCCUAGUCAGGACCGAGCAGGGGAGUAGGAUAGGAAUCCCCGCCGCACCUUUGUACGAGCCUGACCCCUUCCGUGGGUUUGUUCCUGGGUCGCCGUCAAGCUGCGGUCUCUCCUCCCCCGCCCUUCAGCCCCGCGGUCUCCAGGGGCGGCGCCCUGGGUCUGGAACGCGGUUGCCACCGAGGAGGCGGCGGCCCUGCGUCUGGAACGCCGUUGCCACCGAGGAGGCGGCGGCCCCGAGCGCGCCUGGAAGCCCCGGGCAACCGGCCAGGGUCGGGCACAGGUGGGGUCCGUCAGGCCGCCCGGGGCUCCUCUGUCCCAGCUCUGCGGCCCAGGGGGUGACGUGAUGGCGGCAGCGGUGCUGACGGACCGGGCCCAGGUGUCUGUGACCUUUGAUGAUGUGGCUGUGACUUUCACCAAGGAGGAGUGGGGGCAGCUGGACCUAGCUCAGCGGACCCUGUACCAGGAGGUGAUGCUGGAAAACUGUGGGCUCCUGGUGUCUCUGGGGUGUCCUGUUCCCAAAGCUGAGCUGAUCUGCCACCUAGAGCAUGGGCAGGAGCCAUGGACCAGGAAGGAAGACCUCUCCCAAGACACCUGUCCAGGCGACAAAGGAAAACCUAAGACCACAGAACCUACCACUUGUGAGCCAGCCUUGUCAGAGGGAAUCUCACUUCAGGGACAAGUGACACAAGGAAACUCAGUGGACUCACAGUUGGGGCAAGCCGAGGAUCAGGAUGGGCUAUCAGAAAUGCAGGAAGGACACUUCAGACCAGGAAUAGAUCCCCAGGAGAAGUCUCCUGGGAAGAUGAGCCCUGAAUGUGAUGGUUUAGGGACAGCUGAUGGUGUGUGUUCAAGGAUUGGACAGGAGCAAGUCUCUCCAGGAGAUAGAGUCCGUAGCCAUAACUCAUGUGAGUCAGGUAAAGAUCCCAUGAUUCAGGAAGAGGAAAAUAACUUUAAAUGCAGUGAAUGUGGAAAAGUAUUUAACAAGAAACACCUCCUUGCUGGACAUGAGAAAAUUCACUCUGGAGUUAAGCCCUAUGAAUGCACAGAAUGUGGGAAAACCUUUAUUAAGAGCACACAUCUCCUGCAACAUCACAUGAUCCACACUGGGGAGAGGCCCUAUGAGUGCAUGGAGUGUGGAAAGGCCUUCAACCGCAAGUCAUACCUUACCCAGCACCAGCGGAUUCACAGUGGAGAGAAGCCUUACAAGUGCAAUGAAUGCGGAAAGGCCUUCACCCACCGCUCCAAUUUUGUCUUGCAUAACAGGAGACACACUGGAGAAAAAUCCUUUGUGUGCACAGAAUGUGGCCAAGUCUUUCGACAUAGGCCAGGCUUUCUCCGGCACUAUGUUGUCCACAGUGGUGAGAAUCCCUAUGAGUGCUUGGAGUGUGGCAAGGUCUUCAAACACAGGUCAUAUCUCAUGUGGCACCAGCAGACUCAUACCGGGGAGAAGCCCUAUGAGUGCAGUGAAUGUGGGAAGGUCUUCUUGGAGAGUGCAGCCCUGAUUCACCACUAUGUCAUCCACACUGGAGAGAAGCCCUUUGAGUGCCUCGAGUGUGGGAAGGCUUUCAACCACCGAUCCUACCUCAAGAGGCACCAGCGGAUUCACACUGGGGAGAAGCCCUUCGUGUGCAGUGAAUGUGGAAAGGCCUUCACCCACUGCUCUACUUUUAUCUUGCAUAAAAGGGCCCACACUGGAGAAAAGCCUUUCGAGUGCAAAGAGUGUGGGAAAGCCUUUAGCAAUCGGAAGGACCUCAUUCGCCACUUCAGCAUCCACACUGGAGAGAAGCCCUAUGAGUGCGUGGAGUGUGGAAAGGCCUUCACCCGCAUGUCGGGCCUCACGAGGCACAAGCGGAUUCAUAGUGGAGAGAAGCCCUAUGAAUGUGUUGAGUGUGGGAAAUCGUUUUGCUGGAGCACAAACCUCAUUCGACAUGCCAUUAUCCACACUGGAGAGAAGCCCUAUAAAUGUAGUGAAUGUGGAAAGGCCUUCAGUCGCAGCUCGUCCCUCACUCAGCAUCAAAGGAUGCAUACUGGGAAAAAUCCCAUCAGUGUAACAGAUGUGGGAAGACCUUUUACAAGUGGACAAACCUCAGUUACCCUUCGAGAACUUCUUUUAGGGAAGGACUUUUUGAAUGUAACCACUGAGGCAAAUAUUUUGCCAGAGGAAACAUCUUCCUCUGCAUCUGAUCAACCAUACCAAAGAGAAACCCCACAAGUGUCUUCACUGUGAGAAAACCUUCUGUUGCUGAAUAUUACUUGUCAUCUGAAGAGUCAUAUUAGAAAUUCGUUCAGUCUAGAGCCUUAUUCUCCAUCUGAUAAUUUAUCCUGGAGAGAGACCCAGUGGUUAUUGUGCACAUAGGAGAACCUUCAGCUGCAUCUUUCUCCUUAGUUUACAGUGCAAUUUUAUCUCAGGAAUUAUUUUUAAAAGGAGGAGGGGACAUAGAAAAAAUGAAAUGCAAGCACACAUCUUUUCAGGCUUCUCUGCCAAGCCUAUGGCGCUUUGUCAUGGAUUUCUUAGUGUAUUUGGGGGAAGGGAAAUGUUUCAAGGUAAAGAACCUUGACCCUUUAUGUGCUUGUAUGUACAUUUAUUGCUAUCCAGUGUCAGAACAGUUAGUUUAGGAAAAGUAUGCAAACUUUAAUCGCACAUCUUCUGUAUUCCACAAUAGUACUUACUCUUGAGAAGCAUAACUUUAUGACAACUUAGGGGGCUUGAGCCAUGAAAUACUCACGUUUAAGUCAGUAAGGAUACACAUGUUAACAUUCAGGCUUUUGUCUUGAUGCCCGUCUUUUGGUUUACGUCAUCAUUGUAGCCAUAUGGUAAAUUUUUAUUUGUUAAAUUUUUAAAAAUUACUUAGCUCAAAAUGUCAGUGGUAAAUUUUUAAAUUGAGUAAAGUGAUUCUUCUUUGCUCUUAUUUAAAAUCGACAGCAUUUCUAGUUCCUUUGACAUUCCAUAUAAUUUUUAGGAUUAGUUUGUACUUAUUUACAAAACAGUCUUGUUCAGAUUUUUACAGAAAUUGAGUUAAGUCUGUGGAUUAAUCUGUUAAGAAUUGGUAUCUUUACUAUGUUGGGUCUUGUAGUUCAUGAGUGCAGGAGUAGGCCUCUUAAUUUAUAAUAGUUAAGCAUUCCUUAAAGUAUUUCAUUAAUGUUAAAAAUUUUCAGCGUAUAGAUCCCUAUGCAUUUUUGUUAGAAUUUGCAUCCUAGGGUGCUUUUUUGUUUGUGUGUGUGUGUAAUUUGAGUGAUUGUAAAUGGCAUUGAUGUUUGAACUUUGAAUUGCACACAAUUUUUGGUAGUAUACAGAAAUAUAAUAUUUUUGGACAUUGUUUUGCUACCCUGCAACCUUAUUGAGUUCACUUAUUAUUUUUAGCUAUUUCUUUCGACAGAAUCCUUGGAAUUUUCUAUAUAGAAAUGUCAUCUGCAAAUACAGACCAUUUUUUAUCUUUCAUCUUACCUGUAAUAUACCUUUUAUUUCCUUUUUGUUUGUCUUAUUGCAUUGCACAAGCUGGGACUUCCAUUAUAGCGUUGAAUAGGAAUAGUGAGAAAGGCCAUCCUUACCUGGUUCCUGAUAGUAGGGGGGACAAUGUUCAGUUUUUUGUUUUUUUGUUUUUUGUUUGAGACAGGGUCUCGCUCUGUCACCCAGGCUGGAGUGCAGUGGCACGAUCUUGUCUCACCAUAGCCUUAAGUUCCUGGGCUCAAGUGAUCCCCCCACCUCAGCCCUCACCACCCCCCAGUAGCUGGUACUACAAGCAUGCACCACCAGUCCCAGCUAAUUUUUGUAUUUUUUGGUAGAGACAGGGUUUCACCAUGGUGCCCAGGCUGGUCUUGAACUCCUGGGCUCAAGCAACCUGCUUGCCUGGGUCUCCCAAAGUGCUGGGAUUACAGGCGUGAGCCACAGUGCACAGCAUGUUCAGUUUUUCAUCAUGAAGUAUAAUGUAAGUUUUAUAAAACAUAUGUCCUCUAUAAGGGUAAAAAAUUUCCUCUGUUCCCAGUUUUCUGAGACUCUGUGUUGCUAUGAAUAAGUGUGGAAUUUUGUUCAGUACUUUUUCUCCACCAGUUGAUGUCAUUAUGCUAUUUUCCUUCUACAUCCUAUUGAUGGAAUGUAUUGCUUUGAUCAAGUUUUGAAUAUUGAGCCAGCCUUGCAUCCUUAGAAUAAACCAUACUUGUUUGUAGAGUAUAAUUGUUUUUAUAUAUCAUUUGACAUCAUUCCCUUUGUUUGUAUUUUGUUGAGGAAAUAUUCCUCUAAUUUAUUGGCUAAUAAUGUGUAGUUCUUUUUUCUUUUGUUUCUUAUGUUCUAAAUGUCUUAUGUGUGGUUUUGAUGUCUAGGUGAUCUUGACCUUUCAACAUGAAUUGGAAGGAGUUCUCUUCUAAUUUUUGGAAGACUGUGUAGAAUUGGUGUUAUUUGUUCUUGUCAUGUUUGAUGACCUCUAGUCAACCAUUGGGCCAGAGAUUUUUCUUCUGGAGGCUUUUAAAUUACAUAUUUAUUUUAUUGGAUAGGUAGAACUAUUCGAAGUAUCUAUUUCUUGUGUAAUAAAUUUUGAUAGUCUGUCCUGUUGAAGGAAUAUUUCAUCUGUAUUUGUAGCACUCCCUUAUUCUUUUGAUAGCAGGAUCUGCACUUCUUUUUAUUUUUAAUAUUUAAAAUGUGCAUACUCAUUUUAUGAUUGAGUCUUCUUAGACAUUUAUCAGUUUUAUUGCGCAUCAUGCUGAAAGAUGUAAUUUUUGCUUCAUCUCUCACUUCAGAGAACUAGCACUUUAUAUUAAUGAUUUGUCUCUAUUCUUGAUUUCUUUGAUUUCUGCUCUGAUCGGUAUUAUAUUCCACUUGCUUUGGUUGUAUUUGGCUCUUUCUAACUUUUCAAGGUGGGGUUUUAGAUUAUUGAUUUGAGAUUUUUUUGCUUUUUUAAUGUAAGCAUUACAUUGUAUAAAUUUACCUCAUAUCACUAUUGGUUUGAUCCCACAAGUUUUAAUGUUUUCAUUACAUUUUAAUUCUAAUAGUUUUUAUUUUUUGAGACAUUCUCUCUUAGCCAUGAAUUAUUUAAUAGUAUGCUUAAUUUUCUGGUGUUUGGCAUAUUUGUUACUGAUUUCUAAUUUGUUCCAUGUUUGAUCUGACUGUUUAAAUGUGUUAACAUUUUUUUAUGACCCAGGAUAGGGUCUAUCUUGUUUCGUAUAGCUGCUUGAAAAGAAUGGGUGUUCUGCUGUUACUGGGUGGAGUUUCUAUAAAUGUCUCUAUGAUCCUGCUCAUUGUUAUUCAAGUCAGCUAUGUCCUUGCUGAUUUUCUGUCCAGCAUUUCUGUCAGUUGCUGAGAGGGGUGUUGAAGUCCUGAACAUAGGCCGGGUGCAGUGGCUCACGCCUGUAAUCCUAGCACUUUGAGACCACUAAGGCAGGUGGAUCACCUGAGGCCAGGAGUUCGAGACCAGCCUGGCCAACAUGGCAAAACCCUGUCUACUAAAAAUACAAAAAUUAGCCAGGCAUGGUGGCGUGUGCCUGUAAUCCCAGCUGCUGGGGGGCUGAGGCAGGAGGAUCAGUUGAACGUGGGAGGCAGAGGUUGCAGUGAGCUGAGAUCUCACCACUGCACUCCAGCCUGGGCAACAGAGCGAGACUCUGUCUCAACAACAACAACAAAAAGUCCUGAACAUGAUUGUGGAAGUGUGUUGCUCUUUCAAGUUCUAUCACUUUUUGUUUGCAAAGUUCAAAGCUGUAUUGUUUGGUACAUAUACAUGUAGGUUUGCCAAGUCUUUGUGGUGAAUUGACUCUUCUGUCAUUAUGUGAUGUCAUUUUUUUGCCUUUUAAUAGUCUUGUCAAUACUUUACCUGAUGUUCUCAUAGUGACUCCUGCAUAUUUUGAUUAAUGUUUGCAUGGUUAAUAUUUCUUCAUUUUAUUUUAAAGCUUACCUGUAUCAUUACUUAUGAAGUCAGUUUCUUUGAACAGCAUAUACUCAGGCCAUGCUUUUUUUAUUCAUUCUGCAUAUGUCUCUCUUAAUUGGUAUGUUGAAAUGAUUUACAUUAAAAUAAUUAUUGAUAUUUUAGGGCUUAAGUGUGCCCUUAAAUGAUUUUUGUGUUCUUUUUUAUUGUUCCUCUGUUAUUUGGGGUUGUUUACUAGUCUUCCUAUAGGUUACUUCACCUUUUUUUUUUUUAAUAAUUUGAUUUGAUACAUAUGUAGUGUUUUUUAGUAUAGAUCCUCCUUGACUUAUGAUGGGGUUAUGUCACAAUAAACCCAUUGCAAGUUGAAAAUACUAUGUCAAAUAUGCAUUUAAUACACCUACCCUGCUGAACAUCAUAGCCGAUCUUGCCUUCAGAAUGCUCAGAAAAUUUACAUUAGCCUGCAGUUGGGCAAAAUCAUCUAACACAAGGCCUACUUUAUAAUAAAGUUACUGCAAAGAAUUUUAAAUAAAAAUUCAAGUGUGGUUUCUACUGAAUGCAUGUCGCAUUCGCACCAUUGUAAAGUCAAGUAGUAAGUCGAACCAUCCUAAGUCAGGGACUGUCUGUAUAUAUCUGCAUUUUUUAGUGAUUGUUCUACUAUUACAGUGUAAAUAUAUAACUUAUGACAGUUUAAUAAGUUAUCAGCAAUUUAGCACUUUACUUCCAUUAGGUUCCUUUAGCUUACCUACUAAUGUAACUAUCUUAAGUAAUAGUAAUUCCUCUUCAAAAAUUGAGCGCUAUGUUGCAAGAUGUAAUUUUUCUUUUCCUUUUUUUUGAGACCAAGUCUCACUCUGUCACCCACGCUGGAGUGCUGUGAUGCGAUCUCGGCUCUCUGCAACCUCUGCCUCCCGGGUUCAAGCAAUUAACUGCCUCAGCUUCCCUAGUAAUGGAUUACAGGCGCCCGCCACCACGCCUGGCUAAUUUUUGUAUUUUUAGUAGAGACGGGGUUUCACCAUCUUGGCCAGGUUGGUCUUGAACUCUUGACCUCAUGAUCCACCCGCCUCGGCCCCCCAAAGUGCUGGGGUUACAGGUGUGAGCCACUGCACCCGGCCACAAGAUGUAAUUUUUACUUUAUCUCUCACACGUAUUUUACAAAACGUCAUGAGAAACAUUGUCUCUUGACCUUUUUUUUUUUUUUUUUUUUUUAAAGAGACAGAGUCUCACUCUGUCACCCAGGCUGGAGUGCAGUGGCACGAUCUUGGCUCACUGCAACCUCCGCCUCCUGGGUUCAAGCGAUUCUCCUGCCUCAGCCUCCUGAGUAGCUGGGAUUACAGGUGUGCGCCGCCACACCCAGCUAAUUUUGUAUUUUUAGUAGAGACGGGGUUUCACCAUGUUGCUCAGGCUGGUCUCAAACUCCUGACCUUGUGAUCCGCCAACCUUGGCCUGUCGACCUCUUUACCCAUUCCAUUGUUCAUUCUUCUUUCUUGAAAUCCCAAACCUUCUAUUAACAUUUCUUUUCAGUUAUACACUGAACUUUACUGUAGCCUUUCUUCUAGAGUAACAAAUGUUCUUUGUUUUCCUUCCUCUAAAGAUGUCUUUAUGUUUCCUUCAUUCCCAAAGAAUAUUUUUGUGGAAUAUAAGAUUCAGAGUUGGCAGUUGUUUUCUUUUAGACUUCAGAGAUGUAUCUCUCUGUUCUGUACAUUAUUGUUUAAUAUAAGAAACCUACUAGCAUUCAAAUAAUCAUUCCCUAUUUUACAAUGCAUCAGUUCUGUCAAGCUUCAUUCAAAGUGUUUUUCAUUGUCUCUAGUGUUCAGAAGUUUGGCUGUGAUGUGCGUGGCAUGGAAGUUUUUGGGUGUAUUCUAUUUGGCGCUCCCUGGUGCUUGCCCAGCUUUUUGAUCUGUAGGAUUAUGCCUUUUGCAAAAUUUGGGGAACUUUCAACUAUUAUUUCUUCAAAUAUUUUUUCACCCCCCAGUCUUGUCUUUUUUAGGGACUUCAAUAACAUGAGUGGCAGAUCUUGUUUUACACUCCCAUGGGUCCUUCAGGCUCUCAUCUUUUUUCUUUUUCCAGUCUAUUUUCUGUCUUGUUAAUAUUGAUUAAUUUUUAUUGACCUUCCAUGGUCCUCACUGAUUGUUUUCUUUGUCAUACCUAAUCUGUUGAGUUUGUGCAGUGAGUUUUCAUUUUGGUUUUGUAUUUUCCAGUUGUUUAAUUUCCAUUGGGUGGGUUCUUUUGUACACCUUCUGUUUCUUUGCUUAUUUUUUAACGCCAAAGAAAGACUCUCAGAGAAUAGACAACUAUAUUCCAAAGUCAUGGUUCUCUGGUGGUUUGUCUUGACAUUUGAAUAGAAAUGUUAAACUAUCUGGGGGAAUAGAAAGCCCACAGUCUUCUGAGUUGUGCUACACCAAUAUUUCUAUGAACAGAUCUUACAACUGAGAGUGAUCUGCAGAUUUUUCAGAGUCAUGUUCUCCAUGGAAUGUUUGUAAAAUUCCCUAGCUCUCUGCACUGAGCUGAGAUCGUGCCACUGCACUCCAGCCUGGGCAACAGAGCGAGACUCCAUCUCAAAAAAAAAAAAAAUUCUCUAGCUCUCUAUGCCUUGUUGUAUCCUCAGGAAGGAGUCACCUCUCUUCCAGGAUCACUCUUGCCUUUUGUUAUUGGACACAUUUUCCUACCUCCUGCCCAGUCUUUUUUAGGCUCUCUGUCAUACUUCCUCGCCUAGUCUUUAACUUGUCUCUGAUAACCAGAUUUUUCCCCCAUAAUCUGUAUCUGUAUUCAAGUCUCUAUCCUCAUCCCCAAAUGGAUUUCACCCCGCUUGUCCAUCAGUCUCUGCCCAUUUCUUCUGUCUCCCACAGACAUGGUCUGUGUAGUUGUUCUGCACACUACCCGUCCUCGCCCCUUCUCAUUUCCCUCACUCCACGGACAGCUACAGGAGGGCUUCCAUCAUUUGUCCUCUUACUUCCUUGUUAGAACUUUGUGCUGCUGACCACCACUCUGAACCAAAACUUCUUUCUUGGUUCUUGAAAGUUGCUGUCUUUCUCCUCCAGAGGGUCUGUGUCUUCCUUCCAACUCUUAAACAUUUUUGUUUCCCAGAAUCCAUCAUUGGCCAUUGCUUUUUCACUUGCCAUGAGCUCUGUGAAUGAGAUGGUUCCUGCUGAAGACAUUUACUUUCAAUGAUCUACAGAAUUUCCCAAAUCUAUGUCUCCAGACUGGAUGUUUCUCACGUCUGUGGCCCACUGGGCAUCUUCUGCACUUUCUCUGCAUUUGUAAACACUGAGCCUGUAUGCGUGUCUAUGUGGCCAUGGCCCUGGCCGUGGGGAUGCACCCAUAAUUAUAAUGAGAGCAGGUGAAUGUCAUGUGGCUAUGUAUGAGACAUUGUUGUGAAUGUUUUACAUGCAUCAGCUCUUUCAACAUUUACAGCAUCUGUGUGUGGUAGGUAAUGUUGUUUCCUUCAUUUUGCAGAGCAGAAUAUAGAUAGGCUCAGGUUAAGAAUUUGCCCAAGGUUACACAGUUAUGAAGUUUGGAUUUAGGAAUGGGAGGCCACGUAGACUGGCUUCAGAAUUCAUGUCUUUAACCACUUUAUUGCUUCUCAUGUUGGGGGGUUUGUUUUCUGGUCACUAUUUUUACUAAAGUUGAUUCAACAAUGCUAUAAUCUGUUACUCUCAUUCGACAAUACAUCUUGACUGUUUCUUCAACUUGAGGAAGGUAAACCAAAGCCACUCUUUAAUGGGUGCAAAUAUCUGUUGUAACUAUGUAGAAGAUACAGUGUCUGGGUUUGAGGACAGGGGAGUGGGAAAACUGAGUAGGGAAGCGGUAAGACAUGCAUCUGGCUUUAGGAGUGUUUGAAGUGCCUAAAGAUCAGGGUGAAUUUCCCAAAUUUGAAUCUUGUUGCCCAAGCCACAUUGCAACCACCUCUUUUUCUCUUACCUCGUCCCCACAUCCAGGCACUGCCCCAUUCUGUUCAUUCCACCUUUUUUUUUAGUAGACCCUCCAUAUAUGUGUGUGUUUUGGUGAAUGGCCACACACAGCAAAGUUAUUUUUAUUGCAAUUUUGUUGUUGUUGUUUGAGACACAGAGUCUCAUACUCUGCCACCCAGACUGAAGUGCAGUGGUGCGAUCUCAGUUCACUGCAACCUCCAUCCCCCCAUGUUCAAGCAAUUCUCCUGCCUCAGCCUCCCAAGUAGCUGGGAUUACAGGCAUGGGCCACCAUGCCCGGCUAAUUUUUGUAUUUUUUGUAGACACGGGGUUUCACCAUGUUGGCCAGGCUGGUCUCACACUCCUGACCUCAGGUGAUCCACCCGCCUCGGCCUCCCGAAGUGCUGGCAUUACAGGCAUGAGCCACCACACCCAGCCUUUAUUGCAAUUUUUGGUUCCCUCACAGAAUGUUUACCAUGAAGCUGUGCGUAUAGGUGGUACCAUGUAUGACAUACCUUGACCUCAAAGAUAAUCUACCUGGGCUUUUUUUGUUUGUUUGUUUUGAGAUGGAGUCUCACUCUGUCACCCAUGCUGGUGUGCAGUGGCGUGAUCUUGGCUCACAGCAGCCUCUGCCUCCCGGGUUCAAGCGAUUCUCCUGCCUCAGCCUCCUGAGUAGCUGGGACUACAGGUGCCUGCGACCACACCCAGCUAAUUUUUGUAUUUUUAGUAGUAGUGGGAUUUCACCAUGUUGGCCAGGAUGGCCUCCACCUCCUGACUUCAUGAUCCACCCGCCUCGGCCUCCCAAAGUGCUGGGAUUACAGGCGUGAGCCACCGCACCUGGCCUACCUGGGCUUUUUUGGACAGAUGUACAUGAUUUUAGAAAUUGUUAUGAAUGACUGUCUUGGGAUCCUCAAGAACACCCCCAGGUUUGACGAUUUGCUGAGAAGACUCAGGUCUCAGCAUUCUGUCAUACUCAACAGCUAUGAUUUACUGCAGCAAAAAAAUACAAAGCAAAUAGUAAAGGGAAAAAGCCAAAAUUCAGAGAAAACCAGGCACAAUCUUCUGAGUCUUGUUUCAGUGAAGUCACAGGAUGUGCCUUAUUUAAGUUCCAUCUGGUACUUAUGACAACACAUGCUAUAUGUCCACUGGGAAGCUUAUUAGAGACUCAGUGCCAGGGUUUUUAUUGGGCAUGUUUUCUAGCACAUCCCACAAUUCUGGACUUCCAGAAGGUUAGCAGGGGUUCAGCUUUUCAGCUGAAAACGUUAUCCCCCUUUCAGCUGGGGGGAAAAAAAGGCACCGAAAAACAGGGCAGUGAGCUACUCCUGUUUUGGGUGGGUGGAGCAGUAGUAAGCCUCCCAAAAUCUAAGGUCCCACACUCCAGCAAGGGUGAACCUUGCAAACUCAAAAGGAUAGCAGUCUCCAACCUGCUGUUUUAUACAGUGACUUAAGUGGUACUAAAAUGCUAUAUAAGUCAAAUUUACGUAACAUUAAGCAAAUAAUUUUUUUUCAGCAAAAAAAUAAUGGUCAUGACUUUGUGGUGAAGGCUUAUGUAAUGAUUGUAAUAAAUUCAGGUGGCUCACGCCUGUGAUACCAGCACUUUUGGGAGGCUGAGGCGGGUGGAUCACUUGAGGUCAGGAGUUUGAGACCAGCCUAGCCAACAUGGUGAAAUCCCAUCUCUACAAAAAUGAAAAAUUAGCCGGGCGUAGUGGUACAUGCAUUUAGUCCUAGCUACUUGGGAGGCUGAGGCAGGAAAAUCGCUUGAACCUGGGAGGCAGAGGUUGCAGUGAGCCGAGAUCAUGCCACUGCACUCCAGCCUGGGUGACAGAGUGAGACUGUGUCUCAAAAAAAAAAAAAAAAAAAAAAUGCCUCAGUUUUGUUAAGAGGAAAAAGCAAAUCCUAAGUUACAGUGGAACUUAUGAACACCCUAGCCUAGAGAUUUAAUUUAGUGAUGAAAAGGUACAGAGAGAGUCUUUCAAGAAAGGACCUAGUCUGCUCGCGUUCUCUCUCUCUCUCUCUCUAUAUAUAUAUAUGUAUAUGUGUGUGUACAUAUGGACCACUUCAAGCUACACACACACACACACAUAUACACGUGUAUGAAUAUAUAUAUAUGGCUAUAAGUGGUGCGACUUGCAGGUACUCCCUUUGUUCACCUUUGUAAAGAUGUUAUUGCCAGUUCAGUGUGUAUUUCUAUAGUAUAUAUGUAAACAAUUUGUCAUCCUUUUGUUGCUGCUUUUGAAACUAGUUCAUGGCUUCAGUGGGGGAGAGAUUUAAAUAAUAUGGGUUUAUAAUUUCUGCAUUAUUAAAUGCAGAUAACUUGUGAUUAAAGAGUAUGUUAUUGGAA